GUCCCCCUCGGGGCUUCCCAUCAUGGCCGUCUCCCCGAGCUAUCCGCGCUCCCCCACGAGGGCCGGGGCGCAACGGGUGCCCGAGGACGCGGCUGUGAAACGGGCUGGAGCGAGUAGGGGCGAUCCUGGCCUCGUGACGCGGGGGAAUCCGGAUGUGUGAGCCGGGGGAGCGCCCCGUUUCCCCGACGUGCCAGGGCUGGGGACGCAGCUGGGGCCCUGGCCUCGGAGUCCGCAGCCCGGCCGCGUAGACGGCUUCUGAGAACCGCUUAAACACGUCAUUCCAAGCCCGAGCUAACCCAUCAGGCGGCCGGGGAGCAGCUGCUGUGAAUAAACACAGAAGUGGAGCUGGGGGACUGAUUAGAAGCCUCAUUCAGUGCACCUGGGCCCCAGCAGGCCCAGCCAGGCGUGGAGGAAGAGGCAUUGAGGACUUUCCUUACCUGUUUUUCCAGCUCACCCACUGCCAGCAGAGCAUGUCACGUGCUCCCGCCUGAGCCUCUGGCCGCAGGAAUCAGGUGACCCCAGGCAGCGGGCCAGGCUGCAGGGGCGGGAUCUGCUCCGUCACCCAGGCUGGAGUGCAGUGGUGUGAUCACAGCUCACUGCAGCCUCAAACUCCUGGGCUCAACCAGUCCUCUCACCUCAGCCUCCUGAGUAGCCGGGAUUACAGACCUCCCAGCUAACUGGAACCUGUGUCCACAGAAUGCUGUCCAGUUUCAACGAGUGGUUUUGGCAGGACAGGUUCUGGUUACCACCCAAUGUCACGUGGACAGAGCUAGAAGACCGGGAUGGCCGUGUCUACCCCCACCCCCAGGACUUGUUGGCAGCCCUGCCCCUGGCGCUGGUCCUCCUGGCCAUGCGCCUUGCCUUUGAGAGAUUCAUUGGCCUGCCCCUGAGCCGGUGGCUGGGUGUGAGGGAUCAGACCAGGAGGCAAGUGAAGCCCAACGCCACGCUGGAGAAACACUUCCUCACGGAAGGGCACAGGCCCAAGGAGCCCCAGCUGUCUCUCCUGGCCGCCCAGUGUGGCCUCACGCUGCAGCAGACCCAGCGAUGGUUCCGGAGACGCCGGAACCAGGAUCGACCCCAGCUGACCAAGAAGUUCUGUGAGGCCAGCUGGAGGUUUCUCUUCUACCUGUCCUCCUUCGUGGGCGGCCUCUCGGUCCUGUACCACGAGUCAUGGCUGUGGGCACCAGUAAUGUGCUGGGACAGGUACCCAAACCAGACUCUGAAGCCAUCCCUGUACUGGUGGUACCUCUUGGAGCUGGGUUUCUACCUCUCACUGCUAAUCAGGCUGCCCUUUGAUGUCAAGCGCAAGGAUUUCAAGGAGCAGGUGAUACACCACUUCGUGGCGGUCAUCCUGAUGACCUUCUCCUACAGUGCCAACCUGCUGCGCAUUGGCUCUCUGGUGCUGCUGUUACACGAUUCCUCUGACUACCUGCUGGAGGCCUGUAAGAUGGUCAACUACAUGCAGUAUCAGCAAGUGUGCGACGCUCUCUUCCUCAUCUUCUCCUUUGUCUUCUUCUACACCCGACUGGUCCUCUUUCCCACCCAGAUCCUCUACACCACAUACUACGAGUCCAUCAGCAACAGGGGCCCCUUCUUCGGCUACUACUUCUUCAACGGGCUUCUGAUGUUGCUGCAGCUGCUGCACGUGUUCUGGUCUUGCCUCAUUCUGCGCAUGCUCUAUAGCUUCAUGAAGAAGGGCCAGAUGGAGAAGGACAUUCGUAGUGAUGUAGAAGAAUCAGACUCCAGUGAGGAGGCGGCGGCGGCCCAGGAACCUCUGCAGCUAAAGAACGGGGCAGCUGGAGGGCCCAGGCCAGCCCCCACUGAUGGCCCUCGGAGCCGGGUGGCCGGGCGUCUGACCAACAGGCACACAACAGCCACAUAGCCGGGCGGGGCUGGCUGUAAGGGGUUGCCCCCCCGCCAGUGCCUUGGAUAUUUCUGGGGUGACUGGACUGGCGCCCCUGGGCCACCUUUCUGGAGACAGGGAGGGCCCCACCCGGGGUGGGUGGGAAGGCUGAUGAUCUGUCUCCAGCCCCUUCCUUCUGCCCACCCACCCUUCUUCCCUCUGGGCAACUGGACAGAUCUGGGAGCCAGCAGCUGGAUGCUGUGGCUGGCCAGAGACACCUCCAGGCUGUGGCCUGGGGGCUGGGGGGAGCCCCAGGCUGAAAAGGGUCCAAUUAAAACAAAUGGAGCCAAA